UUUUUUGCAUGUGGAUGUCUGGUUGUCCCAGCACCAUUUGUUGAAGCGAUAUCUUUGUUCCAUAGUAUUGCAUUUGUUCCUUUGUCAAAGAUCAGUUGCUAUACUUAGUUAUUCAGUGCUUCUUUUAGGGCUCUUUUUUCUGUUCUUUUGAUCAAUUUAUCUAGUUUUUCACCAACACCGCUCUGUCUUGAUUAGAGUAGUUUUACAGUAAGCUUUGAAGUUGGGUAAUGCCAGUCCUCCAGGUUUGUUCUUCUUCAACAUCCAGUCGGCUAUUCUGGGUCUUUUGCCUCUCUGUAUAAAUUAUAGAAUCAAGUUUGCCAGUAUUAUAAAAUAUCUUGCUGGGAUUCUGAUUGGCAUUGCAUUGAAUCAAUAGACCAAGUUGAGAAGAACUGACAUCUUCACAAUAUUGAGUCUUCCUAUCUAGGACCAUGGAAUGUCUCUCCAUUUAUAGUUCUUUGAUUUCUUUCAUUGGAGUUUUGAAGUUACCCUUGUGUAGAUCUCGUACAUUUUUUUAAGUCUUAUUUCUAAGUCUGUCAUUUUGUAGAGUGCUAAUAUAAAUGGUAUUGUGUUUUAAAUUUUAAUUUUUCCUUGUUCAUUGCUGGUUUAUAGGUAAGCAACUGACUUUUAUAUAUUAAUCUUAUAUCCUGAAACCUUGCUAAAAUUCCAGAAGUUUUGUGUUGAUUCUACUGGAUUUUCUACAUAGAAAGUCAUGCCAUCUACACAAAAAUUAAGUUUUAUUUCUCGCUUAUCAAUCUGUAUGCCUUUUAUUUCACUUUUUGUCUACCUGCAUUAAUGAGGGUUUCCAGUACCAUGUUGAAAAAGAGUAGUAGGAGGGUAAAUCCUUGUCUUGUUUCUGAACUUAGUGGUGAAGAAAUUUGUCAUCAAGCUUCUUUUUCAAGUUUACUGGGUUUGUGGAGUUUCCAGGUAGAUAAUUUAAGUGUGUUUUACAUGCCUCCCUUAUCUCAGUCCUCUCAUUCUGACUCCUGGCUGCCGAACUUGAUCUAGGAGAAAACUUGCAGACAAGAGAUACUUUAUUUGGAAUGAUACCAUGGUAGAAGUAAAAUUUUGAAAUUUGAAGGACUCUCUCAAUGCAUCAUGUAAUCCUCUCUAUACCCAAAUGUCACUUCCAUAAAUGAAGAUGAAAUUAGCCCAUUGAAUAUUUGAUAACUCACACAUUUUUGUCAGCACAUAUGUCGUAUAUUUUUGUAGAAAUAACAGAAAUAUAAGUAGAGUGCUAAAUUGUACAUCAAAAUAUUCUGAUUUUUUUCUCUCAAUAUGUUUUCUCACAGAUCAUAUUUUUAAUAUUUAACAUGUGGCCUGUUUGGUUAGUAUAUAUAUUUCUCUAGAAAUAAACUGAAUAUUCAAAUCUAAAGUUCUUAAAAAUGCCUAAUAAAAUAAAAUUUUUGUCUAAAAAUGCAUGGGGACUGCAUGUGGCUUAUAAAUGUUAUAUUUACCUUAAAAAAAGCAUUACGUAAAUUUUAAAAAUUAUAUUAGUCAACCAGAAAAUAUCUCAUAUCUGUGUAACCUUAAUAAGGCAUCUAGGGUAAAUUGCAAUUGUUCACAUGUUUUUUUUGUUUUUUUUUUUUUUAAUUCUGGGGUAAGGACACUGUUAGGGGAAUAUAUAUUAUCUAACCUUAGAGAAUUUCACAAUAUUUAUACUUCAAGAAGAGCUGUGUCUGUUGCAAACUAAUUUUUCUGCCAUAAACAAAGAGGGAAUUAUUUCUGAGGACUUUAACUUAUUUAUUUUUCCAAAAGCUUGCCACAUGGCUUCAAAUGCAUUCCACACAAACAAUUAUUGUGAGAAAUGAGAAGUGACAAUGCAUUUAACUCCUUGCAUCCUGUUUUUCAGCAGGCAGAAAUUUGCAUCUUAAAUGAAUAAAAUGUGAUGGAGUAUGCCAAACUCUGCCAUCAUUUGGCCAAAAUGAUACCAAAUGAUUGUGAUUUAUUUACUUCACAAUAGAUAAAAAUAAACUACCCUUAGUUAAAAGUUAGAUGCCUAAAAUGUACUAUAUUUUAUGUUUAUUAAGACAAAAGCUCAGUAAAAAGUCUCUGAACUUCUUAGGAGCAUGAGCUAUGAAAUUAAGACUCUGCUGACUUCUGGCUUCGUUGUUGAAUGGGAUUGUAGGAUAUUAUACCCCUGGUAAUCUAUCUUUUACUAUCAAGAGCUUAGAUAACUAAUGACUGCUUUCUCUUUCUCUUUCUCUCUCUCUGUCUCUUUCUCGCUCUCUCUCAUCUAGAUUGCCAGAAAGCUGAGCUUUUUUUUUGUGCUUACUUGCAACAACCAUUUGUAGGCUAGUCCUGCUAGUGUAAUUUUUUUUCUUCAUUAGCUAAGAUUUGAAAGAAUUUAUAGUAUGAACAGAGGGGUACUAUUCCCAGGAGGGGAGAACAUCGUAAGCAAUUAUGCAAACACAUUAAAUAAAGGAAAAGAGCUGUAUGUUAAGAAAUUUGCAAAGAGUUUCUGAAACCUUGAAAAAAUCAUUUUAAAGCUCUGACCUUCCGCUUCUCUGUAAAAUGGGCAUCACGAUACUCGCAAAAAGCUGCUAUGAGAAUUAGAGUAGACAGUGCAUGUGAAGGUGUUUAGCACAUGAGAUAGACUUAGUAAAUAUUAAUGACAUUUCAUCUGCCUUUGGGUAUUUUUUGAGUUCCUAUUCACAUAUCAAAUAUUUUAAUACUCUUAUAUCAAAGAGUAUGGUUAAACCCAGAUUGUUUUCUACUAGCUGUAUGAGAUAGCAGGCGUUCACAGCCUCUUGAAGCUUCAGUUCCUUUACGCUGAAAUGAGGAAAAGCAGUGCAUGAAUCUUGCAGGACUUCUGGGAAGAUUAAUGCAGGGCCCCCUAACCCUGGGCCACAGAUAGGUACUGGUCUGCUAUGGCCUAUUAGGAACCAGGCCGCACAGCGGGAGGUGAGUGGCAGUCCAGCGAGCGAAACGUCUGUAUUUAUAGCUGCUCCCUGUUGCUCGCUUUACUGCCUGAGCUCUGCCUCCUGUCAGAUCAACGGUGGCAUUAGAUUCUCAUAGAAGCACAAACCCUAUUGUGAACUGCACGUGCAAAGGAUCUAGGUUGCACACUCCUUAUGUGAAUCUAAUGACUGGUGAUCUGUCACUGUCUCUCCCAUCACCCUAAGAUGUGACAAUCUAGUUGCAGGAAAACAGGGUCAGGGCUCCCACUGAUUCUACACCAUGAUGAGUUGUAUAAUUUUUUCCUUCUAUGUUAUAAUACAAUAAUAAUAGAAAUAAAGUACACAAUAAAUGUAAUGUACUUGAAUCAUCCUGAAACCACCAUCCUCCUGCCCGGUCCAUAGAAAAAUUGUCUUCCAUGAAAUCGAUCCCUGGUGCCCAAAAGUUUGGAGGCCACUGGAUUAAAGGAGACAAUGUAUGUAAAUUUUGGCUUAUAAUAAGUUCUUGGAAAGUGCUAGCUGUGUCUUAUCACUGAUUAUAGUAUCCCAAUCAAACCUUGACACUUGGGUUAGGAUUAUUUAUUUCCCUCAAUUUAUAAAUGUGAAAGCGGAGGUACAGAGAGGUUAAACAGCUUGCCCAAAUUCACACAGCAGAUAUGUGACAAAGCAAAAGUUCAAGCUGCCCGACUUCUCAAACCUCACUUUCCCAUUUAUUUUACAUCACUUGCCAUUCCUAUGUUUUUCAUUUAGACCAUAAACACAUUAGCAACAUGAAUUUAUCAUCAACGUAAUAUGGCUAAUACAGUUGAUCCGGAAUUUAGUGAAGCAUAUAUAAUACAUGAGGUUUUCAAUUACCAGUCAUUAUUGAUGGUAGCCAGGUCAAAAGUAUCUUUCAGACAUUCUAGAAGAGUCAUGGAGUUACAAAUUUUUAACAUCUGAAAUCUGAAUCCUUUCCCCACACCCAGGCACUACUUUUAUCUUUAGAAAUGAGCAUUUUUUGAAAGACUCAUUUUAGGAAGCAAGAUUUUGAUUGCCUUUGUCUUAUAUAUUCUACUUUAAAAUUCAGUAUGGUGAACCGGGAAUAAAUAAUCAAUGCCUGUGAUGAGAUAAAGACAGUUUCUUCCCAGCACUUUGAGAGGCUGAGGUGGGCAGAUCAUGAGGUCAGGAGUUUGAGACCAGCCUGGCAAAUAUGGUGAAACCCCGUGUCUACUAAAAAUACAAAAAUUAGCCGGACGUGGUGGCACGUGCCUGUAGUCCCAGCUACUCAGGAGGCUGAGGCAGAAGAAUCGUUUGAACCUGGGAGGCGGAGGUUGCAGUGAGCCAAAAUCACUCCACUUCACUCCAGCCUGGGCAACAGAGUGAGACUCCAUCUGAAAAAACAACGACAACAACAACAACAACCACAAACCAUUUCCACACGUUUUAAUUUAAUUGCUUUUUAAAGAGCACGAGGAAAGACUAAGUUACUCAAAUACAUUUUGUAGACUAUCUGUAAGAAGCAAAAGUAAUCAGCUCAUUAAAUAUAUGCAGGAGAAUAGUAAAUGUAAUGGAAGCCUUUCACCUCUUCAUAAGAGAAUCAAAUGAAUGUGAGUUUGAACUGAAAUCCAGCCUUCACUUAACCCCGCUGCCACCUCUCCUCAAAUCAUUCUCAACUUCACAGUUAAACUGUAUGCAUAUUAUAAGUAGGAGGCUCAUUUAUUGGUUUCAGUGUCUCUCAAACUAAAGUCCAAGGACAUAUCCCACAAGAUGCUCUCAGUGGGGGAUGGAGAAAACAAAUAUGACCAAAGGUAGACAAUUUGUCAACCUGGGUUAAGACCCCUUCAAUUUUUCUAUAGGCUUGAAAUUUUUCACACUCCACAGUUUGGGAGAAAAAAGCCAGAAGCUAUUGCCAAUAUCCUGAUAGAAAUUAACCUAGUACUAUAAUUAAGACAAUUUCAGGUCAUGAUAGGAAAAUCUAUACAUCAGUAUUUAUUAAGGGAAAGUUUGUGGGCGGUAGUUGCACGUGAAAUCUCCUUGUCUGAAAGACAGAGGCAUGGUGGCCAGGCUACCAAGGCAUCAGCAGUCUGCCCAAUCCCAUCCCUUCUCCUCCUGAAUUUAGCCCAGUCUAUAUUUAAUACAAAGACUUAGUCCACAGACUAGUGAACUAAUGUAUUUGCAUUGUACAAAUUUACCUUCGAAAAGUUUUAUACAUAUAUUUUUGUGUAAGUUGGCAUUUUUAUUUAAAUUUUGCAAAUCAUUUGUUGACAGGAUCAAAGGGAAAAUAGCAUUUCACUUCCUCUUUCCAGACACCUAUUUACAAAGUAAAAGUCUCUAUUUUUUUCAGCUUUACCUUUCUGACUUUUUGGAUUACUGCUAUCUAAUAAUUUAUAGUAAAAUUGGUGUAUUUUUAUUCCUCUGUACUCAGGAUUAGCUACUGAAAUUGACAUCUGUUUACAUAAAUUUAGUUUAAGGGUAUAAUUUGGAGAUAAUUUGAAUGUAAUUCCUUCAAUGUAAAUAAUAUAAAAAUGUAGCAUGUUAUGUACAAUCUUCUAGAUAAAUAAAAAUUUAUACAGAUGCUCCUCUAGGAAACUAAACUAAAAUUCUAAAUUUAAACUAAAAUUCUAAGAUUACAUAUUGUAGUUGAAAUCAAGCAUCCUUUAUGAGACGUACCAAAUAUAGCCUCUUCUGUAUGUUUGAAGACAUACCAAGAUUAACUUGCAAAAUUUGUUGUAAUUUCUUAUUUGAUAAUAGAAAUCUGGUUUUCUAUGAUUGACACAUCAAUUGUUAGUGAUUCAUAAGCUAAUCAGUUCUUUAACUGGGUUAAGGCAGGCACAAGUAUUCUCUUUUUUAUCAUCAAAAGAAGAUCUAUCUUGAAAUGAAUUGUUAGUAGACAUAUUUUUAACACAGAGAAUAUUCAAUAUUAAUCAAAUUUAUUUUUGACUUCUCAAAUAUUUUAUCCAUAAGAGAAUUAUUCUGUUUCCUUGCCAUUACAACUUACCUUGCCAUUUUCACGUGGUUAAAAACUAGUUCUUUUUUUUUUUUUUUUUUUUUUUUGAGACAGAGUCUCGCUCAGUCACCCAGGCUAGAGUGCAGUGGCACGAUCUUGGCUCACUGCAAGCUCCGCCUCCCGGGUUCACGCCAUUCUCCUGCCUCAGCCUCCCUAGUAGCUGGGACCACAGGCACCCGCCACCACACCCCGCUAAUUUUUUGUAUUUUUAGUAGAGACGGGGUUUCCCCGUGUUAGCCCGGAUGGUCUCGAUCUCCUGACCUCGUGAUCUGCUCGCCUCGGCCUCCCAAAGCGUAAACAACUAGUUCUUACUCUUUCACUUUUCUGUCUCCUAAGGCUCGAAAUGUAUUGUCUCAUAUACCAAAUACCAAAUGUUUAACUCAAAAUGUACUCAGUCAUUGCUGAGGAAGAAUUAUUUUGUUUAACCCUCAUAAUAUAUUAGUAUUCUUAUACCCAAGAAAUACAUACAGACAUUUAAGUUGAAAUCAGGAGUAUGUGGGGAUGAGAAUGGUUGAUGUCAUAAGUACUCCAGUAUUUAACAGUGAUAUAGUUUGAAUAUGUGUCCUCACCUAAAUCUCGUGUUGAAUUGCAAUCCUCAAAGUUGGAGGUGGGGCCUGGUGGGAGAUGAUCGGAUCGUGGGGGCGGAUUUCUCAUGAAUCGUUUGGCACCAUCUCCUUGGUGCUGUCCUGGUGAUAGUGAGUUCUUAUGAGACCUGGCUGUUGAACGGUGUGGCACCCCGCUUGCUCUCUCUUGCUCCCAAUCCCUCCAUUUGAGACACCUUCUCUCUGGCUUCACCCUCCACCAUGACUGAGUGCUUCAUGAGGCCUCCCCUGAAGCAGACGUCUGUGUUAUGCUUCUUGUACAUCCUGCAAAACCAUGAGCCAAUUAAACCUCUUUUCUUUGUAAAUUUCCAGUCUCAGGUAGUUCUUUAUUGCAAUGCAGGAACAGCCCAAUACAAACAGGUAUAGCAGGUGUGUCAUAAUUUAAGUCAAACCAGUGACUAAAAUAGCAUUCUAACCAGACCCUUCCAGCUCUUACAGCAGUAAGCUCCCUUAGGAAGAUUUGAUAUUGACCCUGUUUUAGGGAAGCUUUGAUGUAUUUGCUGAGGCAUUUGUUGACUUUCAAAAGCAACUUCAAUUUAAGGCAUUUUGUACAUACAUAACAUACUGUUAGUACAAACUUAUGAAGGGUUUCCAAUAUAUCCUGAUAAAAAUCCUCUCUCUUUGGAGUUACAUAAUUAUAGAGCACAGAAAAAAAAAUGGAGUUUGACCCAAUAUGAACUUGAAGGAAUCAGGAUUGGCAGUGUGUGUAAAAAUAGACAUACAAAGGAAAUCUUUUAGAAUAUAUUUUAUUAUUCAGAUUUAUAUUAAAAUGAAUUAGAUUAUGGUCCUCCCACAUUUCUGUGGCAGCAUCCAGAAUUCUAUUAUAUUUACUUCCAAUUACUGCAGCAAACCUAGACUUCAACUAUUAGCCAAAGGCUAAAGAUGCUCCUUUGCAGUUGCCAAUAUAUAGACCAGUUUCAGGCUCUCCAGUGGUGGACAGAUGGUCAUUCCCAGGCUAAUAUUGCCCUAUUUCCAUGCAAGAGGAGCUAUUUUAGACCUUUAGAGUUAUGGUUCCAGUGAAAUCAGAGACUUUGGGAAGACAGUGAAUCUUUGAGGAUACGAGAGGACAAUAGACCUUCUUCAUUCUCCUGGAAGGCAGCUUCCUUCCAGAAUUAUUCACUGAAAAUCUCUGCUUCACAAAUUCUCUGGAAUUCUCAAGUGGUGACAUGAUAAUAUUGGUUUUCUAUCAUUACAAUGAAUAUAAAUAUGCAAUUUUUUGUUUUUCACUAAAUAUUUCAAGUGAUUCCUGAUGCUGAAAUACAAUACUACGUGAAUUAUGCUAAGUUGUCAAAAGACUUCUUGAUGCACUGGUUUUAUAGACAGGCAUGAAAUUUCAUUGCAUAAUUGGAUGUGGGUUGUGCACAUAGGAGAGGGAGGUACAGCCAGCCUUCCAUACCCACAGAUUAAACCAAUCUCAGAUUUAGUAUACUAAAAAAAACCGCAACAAAAUAACGUACAACAAUAAAUAAUAGCACAAAUUCAAAAACCAGUGCAGUCUGACAACUAUUUAAAUGGCCGUUACAUUGUACUAGAUAUUACAAGUAAUCUAGAGAUGAUUUAAGAUACAUGGGAGAAUAUGCAUAGGGUAUAUGCAAAUUCUAUGACAUUUCAUAUAAGGGACAUGAGCAUCCAAGGAUGUUGGCAUUCAAGGGGCUCCUGGAACCAAUGCCCCAAGGAUACUGAGUGAUGACUGAAUAUUGUUUUCUUUUCUUUUCUUUUCUUUUUUGCCAUAGUGCUCUUCUUACAGGGUGAUGAAGAAACACCCCUAUCAAAAGAUGGGUGUGUGUUCUCAUCUGUUGAAUGUAGGCAGACUGUUGUAACUUCCUCAUCCCAUAAACAGUGGUGUGCAAUUUCCAAACCAUGUCACAAAAGCCUUUGUGCCAUCCUUCUUGCUUUCUUGAAUUGCUUGUAAUUAGGGAGUUGUAGAUACCAUGUCAUGAGGAUCUUGAAGAAACCCUGGAGAGUGAGAGGGUCACAUGGAGACAAGUUGUGGCCGUUGGCCACCAGCCGUCACCAACUUGCCAGCCAUGUGAGUGAGCCUCUUGGAAGCUGGGGCCAGAGUCCCACCCAAUCCCUUAGUAGAUCGUCCGGGUCUAGCCAACAUGUGACUACAACUGCAUGAAAGACCUUAAAUGAGACCUACUCAGCCAAACUCUUCCUAAGUCCUGUCCAAACAAAACCAUGAAGGAUAAGAAAUGGUUAUUAUUAUUUUAAGCUACCACCUUUUGGUGUGAUUAUUAUAUGCAAUAAUAGGUAGCAGACACUGGCUUUGGUUGGACAUGUAUGUUCUCUGCAUAUUCUGCUUUUGUGCAUGUGGAGAAAUGGGCUUUCUGGGCUGCUGACAAUGAGGAGGUAGAGAUGUUGUUCAGGCAGAUGCGUUUAGACUUCGAGUCCACUUUCUCCUUCCAAGAACUAUGUGGCCUUACAAAUGCUGGGGUUGGUUUAAGAAAACAGAACUCUUAAUGUUUGUAAACAUUCCUGUACGAGAGUUCAUCCAUCAUUUGUGUCUCUCUAGAAAGGUCAUACGCAGAAAAUGUAGUGGUGUAGCAAAAUUUUGAACUUUUCAGAGCUGGCAAAAUCCUUUCUUUAGUGUAUAGUAUUACUACUCAUGUCCAUUAUGAACCAUGAGCCCAGGGAGACUCUGCUGAGACAGGCUGCAUCUCCUCCAGCCUUAUCCUCCUAAGAUCAGGCAUCCUACCUAAGGGGAGCAUAGAAUUUAGCCCCUGUUUGUGGGGUGGUGUGGAUUCUUCCCACCUGUCUAAUCCACCUGAGAAACAGUAGUGAAAAAAAGAAGAAAAUGACAAAAAUCGAGCUGAUUUUUGUAUCUACAUAUGUAGAUAAUAUAUGCUAUAUACACAUGCACAUAGAAUGUAUACGUAUUAUAUUUAUAUAUGUAUGGUCAUUUUUGACCACUCACAAUAUACAAGACAUGAUAAUUUUCAACGUGUCAAGUUAGAAAUUACCAUUCUACCUCACUAAAUUAUCUCAAAAAUCUUGAUACCUAGUAUUUAUAUAUUUUAUAAAUUAAGUAACCUAAGUCUAAACAAGACGACUGGUUCACAGACCACUAUCCUACAUGCAAGCUGCAAUAGGAAAAUAAUUUCUCAGCAGUGAUUUUUUACAAGUGAAAAUAACAUUUAAAAAUUACAGAAAAGCCGAUGAAUGGAAAUAAUCAGUGACAGAUGUGGUUUAAGAUAUAAAAAUGAAAUCUGAAUCCAUUGUCCCCAGUGUGUAAAAAUGUUUUACGUUGUUUCUUGAAAAUUCUCAUUGGAUGACCCUCUCUUGUUGUCAUAUUAAUUCUGAAAUUCUGAUUUUAGUCUAUUUUCAUUUUCACAACAGAACCAGGAACAAAAAGUGUACCCUAGGGGCAUCCAAUUAACAAUAAGCAACUAUUGUAUGUUUGUUGGAACAUACGUGUCAGGAGGGCCGAAAGCAUAGCUGACGUGAUAAGAUAUACAAACAAAAUUAAUGGGAUAAAACAGUAUGAUGGCAUCAAGUAAAACGUUUUUGUUUACAUUUUUGUGUAGUACAGAGGUUACAAUCAGAAAAGGAGUUGUCAGCUCAAGAAAUUGAAUAAAUUAAAUAAUAAAUUAAUGAAUGGAAUAUUUCUGUUGGGAAAUCACACACAGCACAUUAAAUGAAGUUCAUUAGAAAGUGGGAGCUACAGGAUGAAACUGACAGGCAAGGGAUGCUGAAUUAUGGUCGUCUUGUAAAAUUUAAUACCACAUUUCUCAGCUUUAAAGUAUUAAACCUACCAAAAACACUAAACCUGCAUCCCACCUUUGUAACACUUUUGAAAACCCCAUAACCUCACCUGCUGUUAAUUCUAGAUCUUUACAGAUUCAAAGAAUAUAUAUAUAUAUAUGCACACAUAUGAGUUUCUCAUGUUAUUUGCCUUUUUAGUUUUUUGAGAAAUAGGCCUUGUGUGGUUUUCCAAAUAAGUACAAAUUGUACUGACAGCAUAUAUUUUUAUCUCCUCAAGAAGACAGUUCCUUGUCAUUGUUCUUUCCAGCAACUUGACAUUUUAUUUAGGUAACCUGUUCUCCACUUUGUAAUAUGUUAGCUAUCAUCCCAGCAAAAUUGUUCUAUAUUCUACAGAGUGGUAGUUUAUUUUUUUUUUGGAAAUACGGACAAAGCAUUCAAUUAUUUGUCGCCAUGACCGCUCUCGGGGUUAGUUAACUACAUAUGCAACUAAAAUUGGAUAAAUGUAAUUAAGAAAAUUGGUAUUGUAGAGGUUUCAUUGUUCUAUAGAAUUAGAGAAUUCUACCAACUGAAUUUAUAACCUGAGCAUGAAAACCAGAUCCUUUUUCAUAUUUAAAUAUUAACCAGAGUAAGCCAUGUACUACCUUAACAAUAAAAAUAAAAUUAAACAAACUCAAAAAGUUUGAAGAAAUAAAAUGAUAAAAGCUAAGUGAAUUCUUUGAGCUGCAGCUUUUUUACCGUGCUGCACAGUUGCCUGGCUUAGGUCAGAACCUUUUCAAGAAAGGUUCCAUCCUGCCACGGCUCUUUGAAUUUUUCUUAAAUCUUUUAUGUUUAAAGAUAUCUAAUUAUAUUCUAUUUUAAUACUUGGAUAAAUUAAGAAUUUUUAAAAAUUCUUCAUUUUUGUAAAGUAUUAAUAAAGUAAUUUUUUAAAAGUAAAAGAAUAAAUUCAAGCAUUCCAAUCUGUUAAAAUAUCCUUUACAAUGUACUAACCGGAUUAUAUUAUCGUGUGUUUCGCCUCAUUUUUGUUAUACAAAUUUUCAUGUAUUAAGAUGAUCCAUGGCAGGGCACAGUGGUUCACACCUGUAAUCUCAGCUCUUUGAGAGGCCAAGGAGGGAGGAUUGCUUGAGCCCAGGAGUUGGAGACCAGCCUGGGCAACAUAGGGAAAACCUGUCUCUACAAAUAUUUGUAAAAUUUGCUCUCAGAUACUCAAAAGGCUGAGGUGGGUGAACUGCUGGAGUCUAGGAGGCUGAGGCCACAGUGGGCCAGUGAUCCCACCACUGCUCUCCAGCCCUGGUGACAGAGAGAGAUGCUGUCCCCAAAAAAGAAAAAAUCCACGUGAUAUUUACUUCCCUAGCACAUGACAUCAUGUUGCUGUAUCCUGAUUUGACUAUCAGUUAUUGUAUUUUUAAAUAUUUUGGUUUUCUUUUUGUUUCUUUUUUUUAAAAUUAUUUUAACUGUAAAUCAUACAUAGUAUGAACCCCUAUAUACAGAUUAGGCUAUUUACUUAGGAUCUGAUCCCAAAGUUCAGCAGAAGUUGAACAAUACAAAUUAUAACAUAUUCCCAGAUUGUUCUUUAGAGAAAAUAAAUGAAUGAACUGACAAUAUAUGCAUACAUGUUACAUUCUCCCACCCACUCACCAUUUUAUAUAACAGCUUAAUUUUUUUAUUUUAAUGCUUAAAAAUAGAUUUAAUUUGCAACUCUCCAACUGCUUUUGCAGUGAUGCAUUUUUUCCACAGGACAGUUUUCUUUUUUAUUGUUAUUUGGAACAAGGGCAUGUAGGCAAAAGAUGUAAAUGCUUUCCACAGCCUGUUGCUUCCCCAGUGGUUCUCCACCUCACCUGCAUGUUGCUGUCAAUUCAAGAACUUUAAGAAACCCUGAUGCCCAGGACACCCCAAUUCCAGUUAAAUCAGAGUCCUGGGAGUGGAACUCAGGCAUCAGUACAUUUUAAAGCUUCUCAAAUGCUUCUAUCAGCCAUCCAGGUUUGGGAAUGACUCAUCUCAAUUGAUCAUGGAGUCUCAGCUGGGUGUGAUGGGAGAUUGGAAGGAAAACAGUAGGCUUAACUUUAUUAUAUGGGGCAAUCGGAAUUAAGCUGUGUUGUCAGCCUUCCUCCCAUCUAGUGCCCUCAAACAAACCCUUCCCUGGCCCUGAAUCUUCUCUCAUUGCCUAUGUCCUUGCCUGUCACAGUCUUUCUGCAUUGAAACAGUCCAUGAAAAAGGUCUCCUGAUCUAAACUACCCUGUAAUUAGCCUGAUAAGUACCUCAUCUCCUACUUGUAUGCUUUUUCUGAUCUGUUUCCCUGUAGAGUGAAAUCUUACUUUCUGAACAUCCAAAUCCUGAUGAGGUUUUACUGUCAAUGAACAACUGAUAUUUUUACGUGAAUUAAGAGACACAGCAAUUCCACUUCAUCCCAGUGUUUUUACCAGCUACUUGGACACACUCGCCUACUGGAUUUGACCUCUGUGAAUACCAAUGCUGGCCUGGGUGUCAGUAUUUGCUAGAAGCCCCUGUGUGGGUUUGUCUUCCCUUAGCUUUAGCCAGGAAGACAUCUGGCCUCAGCAAGCACACUGCUGCUGUGAUUCUUUUGCUUCUAUUAAGUGCAAAUGAAUGCACUUUAUGUUGAUGGUGUAUUGCAUAAGACUAAUUUCUGGAUUAGCGAAAAAGAGCUCUUUUUCAUUUAUCAGACAUUUUCUUUCUUACAUCUUAUUUUCCUUCAGCUUCAAACCAUGUCUGCCUCACCCAUAUCAGUAACCACAUUAAUAAUGACGAGAAUAAUUAACUUUCAUUGCAACCUUUUUCCAUCCUUAUAACAUAAGUCAUGGCUGGGUGCAGUGGCUCACCCCUGUAAUCUGAACAUUUGGGACUACUAGGUAGGAGGAUCUCUUGAGCCCAGAAGUUUAAGGCCAGUCUGAGCAAUAUAGGGAGACCCUGUCUCUAUAAAGAUAUUUAAAAAAUUAGCCAGGCAUAGUGGUGCAUGCCUGUGGUCCCAGCUAUACAGGAGGCUGAGGUGGGAGGAUUGCUUGAGCUGGGAGGAGGUCAGAGCUAUAGUGAGCCAUGAUCACGCCACUGGAUUCCAGCCUGUGCGACAGCCCUGUCUCAAAAAACAAAACAAAAACAACAAAAACAAGAAAGCCAUAAGUCUUUUACAAAUGCUGUCUCCUUUAAUUUUAACAACCUACAAAACAGUUACUGUAUUUAUCCCCAGUUUUUCAGAUGAAGAAACAGUAGAUUGAAUAAUGUUUAUUGGCCAAGGUUCAAGAAAUGACAGAGCUGGAGGAUUUAAACCUAGCAUUGCUUAAUUCCCAGAGCCUGAGCUGUUGACCAUGUUUUAUGAAAACUAGAUUUCUUAAAAAAAAAAUAAUUGAGGCCCUUACAAAGUCUAUUCCUGACCUCCAUUUAUAUCCCCUUUGUUCCCACUCACUGCCAUUUUUACCUACCUUUCCUCAAGCACUGCUGACCAACUGAUUGUUCCUGGAUCUGUGACAACUGCAUGACUUGCCAUGUGCUGUUUCUCAGGUCUGAGAUUUUUGCUCUCUCCUUCAAGAUAUGAACAGUAAUGGCACAUAUUUUGGUUAUGAGUCACUCAGAGGACUGUGGAUUGAAUGAACUGUAUCCAUCCCCAUCAUGAUGUACAGAACCAAGUCUCUUCACUACACUUGUGUUCUGAUUAGUGGCCAAAUAAAUGACAGUCAGAACUUCAGCUAAGGUACAAUAAGGUUUUGCUGUGGCGUGGCACCUGGUCUCUUUCUAGAAGGAAAGUUCAACAUACAGCACAAUUCUGGACACAUUGUAUUGGUUUGAUGCUCCUACCUGGAACAGGUGGAGCUGGUCUCUUGGGCAGCCUGACAUCUGGUCCACUCCUCUGUCCUAUGCCGGGAUCAUCAUGACCGUAGAGAUUAUGUCACUGUUUUGCAUCCUUGUUACAUAACUCAGUUCCUGGUAGAUUACUAUGUCAGAGAGUCACAAUGACCUUGCACAAUAACAGUACAACCUCGCCUUUGUUUCCAAACAUCAGCUCCUCCUGGAUACACAGCCCCUCCGAUGCAGGGCUGCCCCCGGGAACCGUCACUCAUUUCGGCAGCUACAAUGUUUCUCGAGCAGCUGGCAAUUUCUCCUCUCCAGACGGUACCACCGAUGACCCUCUGGGAGGUCAUACCGUCUGGCAAGUGGUCUUCAUCGCUUUCUUAACGGGCAUCCUGGCCUUGGUGACCAUCAUCGGCAACAUCCUGGUAAUUGUGUCAUUUAAGGUCAACAAGCAGCUGAAGACGGUCAACAACUACUUCCUCUUAAGCCUGGCCUGUGCCGAUCUGAUUAUCGGGGUCAUUUCAAUGAAUCUGUUUACGACCUACAUCAUCAUGAAUCGAUGGGCCUUAGGGAACUUGGCCUGUGACCUCUGGCUUGCCAUUGACUACGUAGCCAGCAAUGCCUCUGUUAUGAAUCUUCUGGUCAUCAGCUUUGACAGAUACUUUUCCAUCACGAGGCCGCUCACGUACCGAGCCAAACGAACAACAAAGAGAGCCGGUGUGAUGAUCGGUCUGGCUUGGGUCAUCUCCUUUGUCCUUUGGGCUCCUGCCAUCUUGUUCUGGCAAUACUUUGUUGGAAAGAGAACUGUGCCUCCGGGAGAGUGCUUCAUUCAGUUCCUCAGUGAGCCCACCAUUACUUUUGGCACAGCCAUCGCUGCUUUUUAUAUGCCUGUCACCAUUAUGACUAUUUUAUACUGGAGGAUCUAUAAGGAAACUGAAAAGCGUACCAAAGAGCUUGCUGGCCUGCAAGCCUCUGGGACAGAGGCAGAGACAGAAAACUUUGUCCACCCCACGGGCAGUUCUCGAAGCUGCAGCAGUUACGAACUUCAACAGCAAAGCAUGAAACGCUCCAACAGGAGGAAGUAUGGCCGCUGCCACUUCUGGUUCACAACCAAGAGCUGGAAACCCAGCUCCGAGCAGAUGGACCAAGACCACAGCAGCAGUGACAGUUGGAACAACAAUGAUGCUGCUGCCUCCCUGGAGAACUCCGCCUCCUCCGACGAGGAGGACAUUGGCUCCGAGACGAGAGCCAUCUACUCCAUCGUGCUCAAGCUUCCGGGUCACAGCACCAUCCUCAACUCCACCAAGUUACCCUCAUCGGACAACCUGCAGGUGCCUGAGGAGGAGCUGGGGAUGGUGGACUUGGAGAGGAAAGCCGACAAGCUGCAGGCCCAGAAGAGCGUGGACGAUGGAGGCAGUUUUCCAAAAAGCUUCUCCAAGCUUCCCAUCCAGCUAGAGUCAGCCGUGGACACAGCUAAGACUUCUGACGUCAACUCCUCAGUGGGUAAGAGCACGGCCACUCUACCUCUGUCCUUCAAGGAAGCCACUCUGGCCAAGAGGUUUGCUCUGAAGACCAGAAGUCAGAUCACUAAGCGGAAAAGGAUGUCCCUGGUCAAGGAGAAGAAAGCGGCCCAGACCCUCAGUGCGAUCUUGCUUGCCUUCAUCAUCACUUGGACCCCAUACAACAUCAUGGUUCUGGUGAACACCUUUUGUGACAGCUGCAUACCCAAAACCUUUUGGAAUCUGGGCUACUGGCUGUGCUACAUCAACAGCACCGUGAACCCCGUGUGCUAUGCUCUGUGCAACAAAACAUUCAGAACCACUUUCAAGAUGCUGCUGCUGUGCCAGUGUGACAAAAAAAAGAGGCGCAAGCAGCAGUACCAGCAGAGACAGUCGGUCAUUUUUCACAAGCGCGCACCCGAGCAGGCCUUGUAGAAUGAGGUUGUAUCAAUAGCAGUGACAAAACGCACACAUCAACCCACAGACCUUAGGAGGAGGAAGGCGAGGGCGGGGUGACUUCUGGUGAUGAUAAAAAUGGUUUUAUCACCCAGAUGUGAAAGAAGCUGCCUGUUUACUGAUCCAUUGAAUAAACCCAUUUUAAUAGAAAAAGUCAAUACCAAUUCAGCAAAAAGAAAAAAAAAACAUACUACUGAAUAUAAAGAAAUUUAUUCUGAAAUAGACUUUACGUGUUUUUUUCUUAAAGAGGAGAAAAAUAUUGCUUGACGGCAAUUAUAUACCCAAAGUGAUUUGCCUGGGUCCUUUAAUUCCCAUUAGCUUUGGAAUCUCAGAUGAGCAUAGCUGACCCAGUUCCCACAUUCUUCCCAAGGAUCCCAAAAGUGGGAAUCCAGACCCCAAGUGGAACACUGCAGGCUUACGAAUCUGUGGUUCCAAAAUUAUUUCAUACGUUGCAAAGCUGAAUCUUCUUGUCCCAAUAGAGCUUCCUGUCUUUUCUUUGGUGUGUUGUUAAACUCUAUUUGUGGACUUGAUUCUUGAUUCUUGCAAAGUACUGUUUUGUGCAGUUCAAGUUUCGUACAAAUAAAAAUACUUAAGUAUAUAUAUAUGUGUGAGUUCUGCACGCACACACAUAGUGUAUAUAAUAUCAUGGGAAACACUGAACUGGCAAAUUAUUCCUGCAACAUACGCUUUCAGUACUUUGGUAACUGAAGUUCUCUAGGAUCCUAAUGCAACAUUAACGUGAAAUAAGCCCAGUGUAAUGUUUUUGAAACCAGGGCUGUUUUCCACAGAGAGCAGCCAGGCCUUCCCAGCAGGUCUGUGCAGAGCGGACAGGCUCGUGAGUCAGCUGAGCGCCGUGGCUUCGCCAGACUUGGUGUUAAGCAACCUCCUUUGUUGAUGUCUCAACAGAGCUAAAUCGGGGCCCCUCUGAGCUCAAAGAAUGAACCACAUCCACACGUUUGAAUUUAAUCAUCUAAAUCUGAAUGUUUCAGAACAAAAUUUCUGCUAUCUAAACUGCUUGAAACUCAAUAAUAGUGUCACGUUUGAAUGUCAUACACAGCAAUAUAUAUAUAUGUGUAUAUAUAUAUAUAUGGCAAAGCAAAAAAAAAAACAUGGUAAGAGAGAAUGAAGGAGAACAUUGUGUUUGAUUCUUGCUGAAUGGCACCUUCUCAAAGAAAAUAGGGCUUGCACCUUUGUUAAUCAGCUGUGGCCAGUGCUUUCUGGUGUUCAUUGUGUAACCUUCACCCAGGAAUAGGUGAGGUUUUAGGAAGUUACAUGUCCUCUGAAGAAAGAAUUACACUCUGAAAAGUAAUGCUUCAAAUUGAUUUCCUUACCUUUUGGGAAAAAAAAAAAAUUGUUUUUUUGCAUUCUCCCUUGAAUUGACCAAAAUGUUAACUGUUUCAUUUGGGGAGGGGAUGGGGUGCUGCCAUCAUUGUCGUUGUUGUUGCUGCUGUAGCUGUUGGGGUUUCUUUUCCUGUUGCCGGGGCUGUUUGGGGAGAGGGAGGGGAGGGAGGUGGGAGGGCCGCGGAGAUAUCUUCCCUUUGUACAGGGCAUUCGUGUUGUGAACCCAGAGCUGGGUAGAAGCUGCUUUUGUAUUCAGUGUGAGGUGGUGUUUACAGACGACUUUGACAACAGUAGAAGUGUACUCAGUGGUGUCUGUGUAUCUGAACUAUUUAAUUUCGUGUUAUGUUUAUAUGCAGAAAUAUUUAUGGAUACUACACCAAGUGUUUAUUUAAUGUUGAUAAAUAUGACUCUUCAGUCGUCAGCCAUGGUGUCCUUUCAAAGUGAUUCUUUAAGGUCCACUUGAGCAAUGAAUAGAGUAUAUUGGAGCUUUCCUGUGGCUAAGAAGAAGAAACAUGUCAUCCUGUUGGCAUCACCAAGCACCUAACUCUUUCUAGGUAAUAAAAAGUCAACGGUCACUUCAACGUAAAUGUUUAAAACCACUCUUUAGUUAAAUCUGAUGGGAACUGAACAAAGCUCCACCAUUGUGUCUGAAAUCAUUUUACACAGGGAAAAAAAAAAACAAUCAGCAUAAUUGUAAGAAUGAUUUUUUUGGGCCCACAUUCAACCAAAGAACAAGAAAGAAACAGACGAUUUUCUAAUAUGUACACAGCAAACUACAGAAUGUCAUAUUAUCCACCUGUGAAACAUCUAGUAAGCAAUUGCAUCUAUAUUUUAUUUCUCAAGUUGGCCUGGCACUAAUAAAUAUGUGAAAGCUUAUUCAAGUGUCCCAGUACUUCAGCACUUCCCAUCCUUUUGGAAACUCCUAUCUUGCCUCCCUCCCAAAAGGGCUGUUUCUUUUAUUAAAAAAAAAAAAGAAAUAGAAUUAAAUUUGAGAAAAGGAGAAACCCUGAAAUUUAACAGAACUUUGAGAGUCACUUCCAAUCUCCUUAAACAUGAUUAUCUCCUUAUCCUUGUCCUUUUGUGAUGCUAAUAAUAGCAGAAAAGGAACAAAUCCAAGACUCUAGGUCUCCCUUUUUUGUUUUACUGGUUUUAUUAUAGAAUUGUUUUUAAGCCUCUUAUGGAUGAAAGCUGCAUUUAAAUACUAUCUACUGAUUUUAUAGAAAGGUAUGUCCAUUUCUUGGGUCACUUUCAGAGAAAGAAAACAAGCAAAAUAGGUUCUUUUGAAUAUGAAUAAUUUAAAAGCAUAAUUGAAGAUGUAGUGAGUAUUUAUAAUUGGACCUUAGUUACACGUGCAUUUCUCAAAGGGCUUGUCAUUACAGGAGAUAUUCAGCACUUACCUAAGAUCAAAAUGUCUUCAUCCCAAAUUGGGAAUCGAAUUAUUUCAUGCCAUAUGCAUGAGGUUUGCAGACAUUUCAAGAUUAGCCACUUUGCUUGAAAGAAGAAAAUGAUCAAACCUAAAAUAAACUACACAUGGAGAAUCUCUCUCUCUCUCUCUGCCUCUCUCUCUCUCUUUCUCCCUCUUCUUCCUUCUCUCUCUCUCACAAGCACACACACACACACUCAAUCUCCAUUCUCCAGGCAUUGCCAGAUGGUUAGGAGAAGUGAGCUCUCUCUGGUCCCCUAGAUCCCUCGGCUCUGCUCUCCUUUGCCCAUCAGCUCCCUGUGGCCUCUAUGCUAGUCCUCCCUAUUCUCCUAGUCACCCUUUGCCUCUUAAGCCCAGCCUUGACUCUCUACAUAUUUUUCAUUUCUCUUUACCCUUUAGUGUACAAUAGUUGUAGACUCUGACGGAAUGAAAACAAACAAGAAGCCUAAGCGUUAGACCCUGCUGUGGCUAAAGAUCUAGAAGGCAUAUCAGUUUUCUCUGUCAGGCUUCCUACGUUGCCCUCGUGCAGGGCUCAUUGCUCUGCAGAGCGCUGGAAGCCCCUUCAUGUAUCGAGAGAGAAGCUGGAGCACAGAGCUCUGAUGCACAGUUGGCUGUUUCAGCUCUGACUCAGGGAGGAAAGAAGGAUGCCAAGGCUCUGUCACAGCGGAGAAGUCUAAUACCAGAGUGGCACAGAGAAGGAUUCCAGGGAUCAGUCAGGGUGUCCUGUACCUAUCUGAGUAGAGAUGAUUCAAGGAUGGGGACAUAUUCCAGGAAAUUGCACAAUCUUCCCCUGGCAGCUUCAGAGGACGAGUGAAAAUAGUGCAGUAUAGUCAAAGAAGCAAUGAAUUUAGGAUGAGGAACCUGAAGUUUCUGGACCAGUUUGGUCACUGCUUAGUUACAUGUCCUUAGGAAUGCUUGUCACUUAACCUAAACUUUCUGGGUUUUAUCCUCAUUGCUCAAACUAAGCAACAACACCGAAGCUUCUCUAAUUUGCCUUCUGAUGCCAAAUCGGUCAAAACUGAGGUCAGCAGCUACCAUGACGAAAGUAAAAUGGUAUAUUGGGUGAAUGUUUGAAAAUUUCAGAUUUUAUAUUCUGUAAAGUUAUUUACUUACUCUAUUUCAACACCACAAAAUCUUGAAAUUUGGAAGGUAACCAAGGAAGCUUUGAAAUUUGUUGGCAAACCCGGAGUAGUAUGGUUUCAAAUACCACUCCAACCCAGCACCUGAGGUCGGGCAAACUCACAAAAUAGAGUUUCUAGGUAGCAGGUGUUUGCUUUGGUUUUGCAAUAGCAUUUCUCAUAACAGAACUGAAACUGUAUAGAUUACAACACUCCAAAGUUAUUUUUUUUUAACCUAAAGAACCCUACUUCUAGCACCUCCUCUGAAAGAAUAUUUUGCUCCAAUACCACGUGCAACAAACUUAUUUAGACAGUAUCAACUCUAGCCCUUAAUAGGUUCAAGGACAAGUUUACUGCUUCCUUUCUACACGCUUAAGUUACACUCUCUUCUCCUGUUCUGAUGACUCUAAAUCUUCAGCCUCUCCCAGCAUUAAUGUGUGAGUCAACAUUGCAGACCUGAGAAAGGUUUCUAGAAUGGUAACCCAAUGUUCUUUAGAACUGGAGAAUUCCAUUUUCCUUUUCUGGCUUUAGUGUUAAUGUCUGGGAAGGGAGGCUCAUGAUAAGAAAAUAAAAAUGAGAAAAGAAGAUCUAGUUCAUAAAAUGACUAUACCCCACGUAAGUUUGUAACUGCACAGUGUUUUGUUGUACGGCUCAGAAAUGAGCAAGUGUUAGUAUUAUUAGGCACACAUCACGUUCACAGCUUCGCGCAGAGACGGAUAGUGUAUUUGGAUAUAUGGAAGUCAUCCAAAUGCGUUGCUAGAAUAUCAGGCCUAUGUUUGUUCUGGUAGAACCACAGAGACUCACACAAAGUUCUGACCCUACCACUCUGGUCUGGGCUGAGACCACCCCAAAAAAUCAUCUAGAGAAUCAAAGGGGCUCACAUCUCAGUUGCAUUCUAUUUAAAAGAUAAAGGGGCCAUACUCUCCACUGCAAAGAAGCAUUAGUAAAACUUCCCGCACCCAAAUUAUAAUCCGGCAACCCUAGCUUCAGCUAAAAAGAUUAUCCCCAGAAUCUAAAAGCUUACUAUUGUUCUUUCUUGGAGUCCAAAAUGCUUAGCAGUUCUGCAGUUCACAUACAAAACUCAAAACUCUUUUUAUCCUGUAUUCUGUGAGUUCCUUGAUGAUAGUAAUUGGGUCUUAUUCAUCACUCUGUAUCCUGUGGCUCACACAGAAUCUGGCAAAUUGCAUAUAUUCAAUAAAUGUUGAAUAUCUAAUAACCUCCUUAUUAAUAUAACAAAUAUUAUCAACAUUCUGUGCACAUCAAUGUCCCAUGCUGCUACUGUAGUCAGGAGUUAUUUGGCUGGGAAGUGGAAAGUGUUCACAAACAUGAUGCUUAUCUAAUAAAAUAUCACUGAGCAAUAAGGAGAAAUAUUUUAAAUAGAUUUGAAGUUGUGAACAAAUAAUUUAGAGUCCAAAGAGGAAAAAGAAAAUUAACUCUGUUUUUUAUCCCUAGAACUCAGAAACUUUACUGGAUUGGUCAACAAAGACAAACUUUUUAUUGUAUAAAACAGUAGAAUUCAUGGAAGGGAUAAUUCUUUUGGAACAGGCUUCUCGGUUACUUGCCUUAGUAAAAGAAGUAUCUGGAGGGCCUGGAGAGUUCAUAAACAUAGUUUUCUGUGCAAGUGAAGAUCUGUAGUUUGGCUUAAAAAUCCUUGCAUGUAGUUUUGCUUGGCGUGGAAAGUUAUUAGGAGACAAUCCUUUAUCCUGUUCUGCAAGCAAUCAAACACAUGAUCUCCCUUCUAGCCAUUCCUCAUCCAGUACAUGGGCAUUUCCAGCCUCCUACAUGUAACACUUCAAACUUCCUCUGGGCGUCUGCUUAGAGCUAUGUGAUGGCCACAGUUUGGGCAAAGCCCUUCUUUCUUUUAAAUAUAGGAACUGUUACCAAGUUUGGUGCAGGCUUGAGGAAUAAUUACAUAAAAAUGGGCUUCCACGAUGGUGAAUCAGCAUGCUGAUUUCUCUUGGCAGGAAGCUCUCAGGGAAAUGUCUGUGAAUCAUUUAAAGAUGCUCUCUGGUGGAUAGAGAAACCGCAGUCCAAAAACAGAUGGGUGUAUAUUUGCUUUGUAAGCAAAGGGCAUGUAUCAUACUCGCAUCUAAAACAGUGUCCACAUCUUUGCCAAAGGCACUGAAUUUUACCUUUUUUUAUUACCUCGUGGCCAGCACUUCCUCAGUAGGCAUUUCAGGUGUGUCACAAACCAUGUUCAUUUUUAAUCUUGAAAAAGUCAAUCGUCUGUAGUCUGUACUAUAAAAUGAUGCCUGCAACUUUGUGGUGAAUAUUAUCCCCAAGUUAACAGUGAAAUAAGUAAAUAAAACUAUUAUUGAACAAA